CUGUUUUGCUAUGUGACCCUGACCUAGUUCCUUGCCCUCUCUUGAUCUCAGUUGCUUUAUCUGUAAAAUUUCACAUUUUUCAGCAAGUCAACCUUCCAUGUUCCUCUCAUUAAAAUAUACUCACCCCUGGGACUGUGCAAAGGAGAUUUGUAAAGUCAGGGGGUUAUUGUGUUACAUAUUCCUUGUAGGUGGGAAACCUAAAGUCUUAUUUUUCUAUUAAAAAUAUAUGAAGUAGUUGAAUGAAAGGUUAAAAUGAAUUUUUAAGGUAAAACUUAAGACCCCAAGAAAAAUGGAAUUGCCAACUAUGGCUUAUAGGUAGCUUUGGGAGCAAACUCUUUCCAUCUCCCAGGGACUGGGUGCCUUCAGAGACACCUGGGGGCAAAGUGAAGGAAGGCUGGAGAUAAGAAAGGCCCCUUCUGCCUCCAAAACUCUGAUUCUGUAAGCCUUCAGUCAUGUCUCACAUUAUACACACAAACCAUGCUGGGUUUGUUUUCUUGGAGUAAUACUUGAGUUUUUAAAGCUCUUUAUUUCAACCCCAAAAGGCAAACAUUACAGCAAAGUCACAUCUUAUGCUGUAGUCUAAUGUCAGAGAAUUUAAUUAAAACAGAGUACUCUUGAAAAAUCCCUCGAAUUUCCCAAAGUCAGUAUGAUACCAUUUCACAGCAAGACCAGCAGACCUAGUGUUUCCUCUCGUGUUGGGAUUAUUUGCAGUUGCUUUGAACACCAUAGAAGCCUUGCAUUUACAAUUGUAGUAGGCCCAAGGCCCUCUCAGUCCAGGGGAAGCUCCUGAGAAACAAGAGAGACUGAGGGAACCACAGAUCUUAUCUGCCAUCUCAAGCUCAUGCUAGGGCAGAGAUCAGCAUCCCCAGAACACACCUGUGUUAAGUCAAAGACCUUGGACCCAAUGGUCAUCUUCUUCACCAGUGGGACCACAGGCUUCCCCAAGAUGGCAAAACACUCCCAUGGGUUGGCCUUACAACCCUCCUUCCCAGGAAGUAGGAAAUUACGGAGCCUGAAGACAUCUGAUGUCUCCUGGUGCCUGUCGGACUCAGGAUGGAUUGUGGCUACCAUUUGGACCCUGGUAGAACCAUGGACAGCGGGUUGUACAGUCUUUAUCCACCAUCUGCCACAGUUUGACACCAAGGUCAUCAUACAGACAUUGUUGAAAUACCCCAUUAACCACUUUUGGGGGGUAUCAUCUAUAUAUCGAAUGAUUCUGCAGCAGGAUUUCACCAGCAUCAGGUUCCCUGCCCUGGAGCACUGCUAUACUGGCGGGGAGGUCGUGUUGCCCAAGGAUCAGGAGGAGUGGAAAAGACGGACGGGCCUUCUGCUCUACGAGAACUAUGGGCAGUCGGAAACGGGACUAAUUUGUGCCACCUACUGGGGAAUGAAGAUCAAGCCGGGUUUCAUGGGGAAGGCCACUCCACCCUACGACGUCCAGGUCAUUGAUGACAAGGGCAGCAUCCUGCCACCUAACACAGAAGGAAACAUUGGCAUCAGAAUCAAACCUGUCAGGCCUGUGAGCCUCUUCAUGUGCUAUGAGGGUGACCCAGAGAAGACAGCUAAAGUGGAAUGUGGGGACUUCUACAACACUGGGGACAGAGGUAAGAUGGAUGAAGAGGGCUACAUUUGUUUCCUGGGGAGGAGUGAUGACAUCAUUAAUGCCUCUGGGUAUCGCAUCGGGCCUGCAGAGGUUGAAAGCGCUUUGGUGGAGCACCCAGCGGUGGCGGAGUCAGCCGUGGUGGGCAGCCCAGACCCGAUUCGAGGGGAGGUGGUGAAGGCCUUUAUUGUCCUGACCCCACAGUUCCUGUCCCAUGACAAGGAUCAGCUGACCAAGGAACUGCAGCAGCAUGUCAAGUCAGUGACAGCCCCAUACAAGUACCCAAGGAAGGUGGAGUUUGUCUCAGAGCUGCCAAAAACCAUCACUGGCAAGAUUGAACGGAAGGAACUUCGGAAAAAGGAGACUGGUCAGAUGUAAUCGGCAGUGAACUCAGAACGCACUGCACACCUAAGGCAAAUCCCUGGCCACUUUAGUCUCCCCACUAUGGUGAGGACGAGGGUGGGGCAUUGAGAGUGUUGAUUUGGGAAAGUAUCAGGAGUGCCAUGAUUCCAAUGUUUUCCUUCUUUUAAAUUAAAUUCAGUUGCUCUGCUUCCUCCAAGUCCUCUGUAUCUUUAGAAUUUCCCAGGUGAGCACUCAUAACGCAAGUAAUAAAAUACUGAUAUCAACAA